GCGGGCCCGCGAGAUGCCGGUGUUGGCGGCCCGAGCGGCUGCAGUUGCAGGGGCGGGGGAGGCGGCGGCGGGGCCCGGGAGAGGGGUGGCGUGGGGGACCGGCGCGUAGCCGGGACCAUGGAGGGGCAGAGCGGCCGCUGCAAGAUCGUGGUGGUGGGAGACGCAGAGUGCGGCAAGACGGCGCUGCUGCAGGUGUUCGCCAAGGACGCCUAUCCCGGGAGUUAUGUCCCCACCGUGUUUGAGAACUACACUGCGAGCUUUGAGAUCGACAAGCGCCGCAUUGAGCUCAACAUGUGGGACACUUCAGGUUCCUCUUACUAUGAUAAUGUCCGGCCUCUGGCCUAUCCUGAUUCUGAUGCUGUGCUCAUCUGCUUCGACAUUAGCCGACCAGAAACACUGGACAGUGUUCUCAAGAAGUGGCAAGGAGAGACUCAAGAGUUCUGCCCCAAUGCCAAGGUUGUGCUGGUUGGCUGUAAACUGGACAUGCGGACUGACCUGGCCACACUGAGGGAGCUGUCCAAGCAGAGGCUUAUCCCUGUUACACAUGAGCAGGGCACUGUGCUGGCCAAGCAGGUGGGGGCUGUGUCCUAUGUUGAGUGCUCCUCCCGGUCCUCUGAGCGCAGCGUCAGGGAUGUCUUCCAUGUGGCUACAGUGGCCUCCCUUGGCCGUGGCCAUAGGCAGCUGCGCCGAACUGACUCACGCCGGGGAAUGCAGCGAUCCGCUCAGCUGUCAGGACGGCCAGACCGGGGGAAUGAGGGCGAGAUACACAAGGAUCGAGCCAAAAGCUGCAACCUCAUGUGAGGGGCUAGGAGAGGGCAGAGUGUGAAGAGGGGUGGUGAGGGACACAAUUGUUCCCCUGCCUGCGCCCAGGCUUCCUGACCUCCUGAUCCUGGCUGGGAAGUUAGGGCAGGCAGAGCGAGCAAUUCUGGGCAGGGGAGCUGGAGGGCAGAAGGGUAUCAUCGUUUCUCAUCUCCUCCUCCCUCCUCUUCUCCAGUGGAUGUUGAGGGAGCUAACAGGGCUGGCAUCUGGGGCAUGAACUGGGAUGGGGCAGGUGGGCGUUAGGGAAGCUGGUAUCAAAUGGUGACCUUGGUGGAGUCUCCUAUGUGAAGAGUACCCUCCCUCUCCACCCCCAGUCCCCAUAUCCUGGUUCUGGCCCAAGGAAAAUGUCCAUUCUAUGACCUUCUCUUUUCCUCUCCUCUCACUUCUGCAGCUAUUCUCACACAUCUAACCUCUAGGCAACAUGCACUAAAUUCAAAAGCAAGGAGAAGCCCUUGCCCCCCAUCAGUCCACCAGCCCUAGAACCUCCCUUGCCUCAACAGUCACCUAAUAAAGCCCACCUCCAUGGAAAACGGCUGUGGCUUUAGUUUUGUUGCUUUUUAAAAAAAUCAAUCUACCAAUCUUUAGCAGUAAGAGGGAAAGUUAGACCUCAGCUGGGGAACUUUCCUGUCCAUGUCCACAGAUAGAGCAGAGGACAAAGCCAUAGGUUGGAUCAGAAGUGUCCUUUUAGGAGUCAGAGUUGGGAGAAGGAGACAUCCUGGGACUGUUCAUCCUAGUUAAUGAAGUGGGCAAUUCUCAGGCCAUUAGGGGGUUUUAGAGCAGACCGACAUAUAAUUAGUCAGCAUUUCUCAGCCCAGCCAGGCCUGCUGCUAGUGUGGGAGGGGUCCUGCUCACCAUCUGUACCCCUGGCUUGGAGCCUGCUGGUACCCUGGGGGUUGUGGGGAUAAGGAGGCAUCAGGCCGGGCGCGCUGGCUCACGCCUGUAAUCCCAGCACUUUGGGAGGCCGAGGUGGGCGGAUCACAAGUUCAGGAGAUCGAGACCAUCCUGGCUAACACGGUGAAACCCCAUCUCUACUAAAAAUACAAAAAAUUAGCCAGGCGCGGUGGCAGUGCCUGUAGUCCCAGCUGCUCGGGAGGCUGAGGCAGGAGAAUGGUGUGAACCCGGGUGAACCUGGGAGGCGGAGCUUGCAGUGAGCCGAGAUUGCGCCACUGCAUUCUAGCCUGGAUGACAGAGCAAGACUCUGUCUCCAAAAAAAAAAAAAAAAAAAAAAAAGAAGGCAUCAAAAGCCUCCACAUCACAGAAGCUACCCCUGUACAGCGUGAAGUUUCCUAAGAGGUCAGUAGUUUGAUUCUGGGGUCUCCUUAGAGGCUCAGGCCAGGGACCUUUCUCUCCUCCCAUGCUGAGUUUCAUGAUGGCUUUCAGGGGAGCAUCAGCUGUUAGAGUCACCCCUACCCUGUCCCUUAAAGGAAAGACGGUGGAGAGGACGGCUGAGCGCCUGUUGUCAGGAAAGACAGUACUGGUCUGUUUUCUCGGGAGUCUGGUUUCAGAUUGUCCUGUAUUCCCUUCCUGGCUCUGGUCCCACUGGCCUCUUUUCGGUGACAUUCUCCCCCAGGAACCAUCCCUGGCCCUUCCCUCCCCCAGCCCUAGCCAGUUCUCCCAGACACACUGGAAGAGAACACUGACCUUACCCAACUAUCUGCUGGGAUCCCACCCAAAUUUAUAGCCCAUUCCUCCCUCAUUCAUUCAUUCAGCAAGUAUGUACUGAACACCAACUGUGUGGCAUACACUGGCUUGGGAGAUUGCAAGGACCAGUCUCUAAGCUUUUGGAGGCCAGCCCAGUGUGGAAGAGAGGUACCUCAGGUGUGAGGGUGCCAUGGCUGAGGGAUAUUUGUACAUGUAUGGGAUGCUAUGGGAGCUCCUUGCAGCCUGAGAAGCCAGUCCUGUGAGCCAGGUCCUGAGGGUUGAAGAGGAGUUUUCCGGGCAGGGAAGGGGUAGGAAAGGCACUCUGGGCAGAGGGUACAGCAUGUGUAAACACGUGGAGAUGAGAAUGAGCAUAGCACUGUUGGGGCUCCCAUGGCAGGGAGAAUAGAAGACAAGGCUAGGAAGGUACACUGAGGCUACUGCAGGGUCCACAGAGGAAUCAGAAUUUCAUUCUGAGGAUGAAUGAAAUCAUCCUCAGAGGAUGAAGCCACCAGGAAUUUCAGGCAGAGAGUGAAGUGAUCAGAGUUGUUUUUUGGAUAGAUGGUUAUCUGGAUGUGGUGUUGGAGCUGGGAGAUUUGGCUCUGAGGUGUGUCAUUUAAAAUAAUAGCUUCUCGGCAGUGGCUCACACCUAUAAUCCCAGCCAAGAUUCCUCCUUUGGGAGGCCAAGCUGGGAGGAUCGCUUGAGGCCAGGAGUUAGAGACUGCAGUGAGCUAUGAUCAUGCCAUUGUCUUCCAGCCUGAGUGUCAGAGUGAGACCCUGUCUCUAAAAAAAAUUAAAAAAUAAAAAAUAAAAAAUAGCUUCUCCUUUCCCUUAUGCCAGGUUCCAGUCUUGAGAGGAAAGGAAUCCCUACCCACCACUCCCUGGAUCAUCAGAUAUCCCUAUCCCAACCUCUCCUAUGGGACUAGUUCAUCUCAGCCAGUCUCAAAGAUUCUAGGAUAACUUCAAUGGCAUUUGAAAUUAUCUAAGUGUGCUUGGAUAACCACCCCCUCAAACUGAGACCUGGUUAGGGACUGACUCAAAGACCCUGAGUCCUCGGCUAAGGGUACAGGAGAGGGCAGGGGCUCCAGGCCCAGCUAGGUGGAUCUCCAUCUGUCUCUGAGGACUGACCCUUUCCCCACAAGGACCUGCCAUAAAAAUCGACUUGCGAUUUUUAGCUGAGUGGCUUCUCUUUUCCACUUUGGACUUCUCAGUGUAUAGCAGGUUCAAGCCUGCAACCACCAAAGUGCAGAGUGUGGAGUGUUUGUGCCCCCUCUUUCCUCCAACCUCCAUAUCCUGCCAUGUGAGCUCAGGGAAUGCAAAUGCAUUUAAAUAUCCAUCUAAAGCAAACAUAAUUAGAAAAAUCAAUCAGCUGGAGGACCCCCCAAAGUUUAAUACAUUUUCAAUACCACCAGGAAUGGAUUUUUGGUCCCUUUCUGCAGGUCUGGGUUGCCAGACGUUUUAUUUCUGGGGAGGAGGGCUCUGGGCUGAGGAGCUCAGUGGGUGGGAGGAGGGAAUGGGACUGUUGCUGAUCCUCAAAGGCCUCUGUAGGAUGGAGGGAGGGGACCUUACUCCCUUCCCCACCCCAGAUGCAGGAGUCACCCAGCUUCCUUCUCUGCGCUGUUUCCUUCACAAAUUAGACAUUGGUUUGGGAAACAAUGUAGCCUCGUUAAACAUUUAAUGAAAUAAACAAAUAAUCACACUGUGA